GCGGCCGGACGGGAGUUCCCCGGAGAAGGAUCCUGCAGCCCGAGUCCCGGUGAGUGCGAGAGGACCCGCGCCCCCUGUCACCCCUCACUUCUCCUGAGUCCCAAGUAAGGAACGGAGCCAACCCUGGGGAGGACCCCCGGUCCCCUCUCCCAGAGUAUACGGAGCCUGAACCUCCCCACUUCCCCCAACUCUGUUCGCGGAUAGGGUCUAGUUGCCUGCUCUCGGACAUCCGUUCAGCAGACACUACCUCUUCGUCACCCCCUGCCCACCCUGACCCGCCUUUACCUCGCGUCUAGAGGACACAGCCAGGGAUCAUCCCGCAGCCCCGAACUCCUUCACAGACCCCCACUAGCCGGGGACGCAGCUCAGGCCCCCUACCCCCAACACAAACACUUCUCUCCUGUAGAGGAUAAAGCUUGGGGUUCAUCCUCCUUCCCUGGAUCACUCCACAGUCCUCAGGCUUCCCCAAUCCAGGGGACUCGGCGCCGGGACGCUGCUAUGGACGACAUUUUCACUCAGUGCCGGGAGGGCAACGCAGUCGCCGUUCGCCUGUGGCUGGACAACACGGAGAACGACCUCAACCAGGGGGACGAUCAUGGCUUCUCCCCCUUGCACUGGGCCUGCCGAGAGGGCCGCUCUGCUGUGGUUGAGAUGUUGAUCAUGCGGGGGGCACGGAUCAAUGUAAUGAACCGUGGGGAUGACACCCCCCUGCAUCUGGCAGCCAGUCAUGGACACCGUGAUAUUGUACAGAAGCUAUUGCAGUACAAGGCAGACAUCAAUGCAGUGAAUGAACACGGGAAUGUGCCCCUGCACUAUGCCUGUUUUUGGGGCCAAGAUCAAGUGGCAGAGGACCUGGUGGCAAAUGGGGCCCUUGUCAGCAUCUGUAACAAGUAUGGAGAGAUGCCUGUGGACAAAGCCAAGGCACCCCUGAGAGAGCUUCUCCGAGAGCGGGCAGAGAAGAUGGGCCAGAAUCUCAACCGUAUUCCAUACAAGGACACAUUCUGGAAGGGGACCACCCGCACUCGGCCCCGAAAUGGAACCCUGAACAAACACUCUGGCAUUGACUUCAAACAGCUUAACUUCCUGACGAAGCUCAACGAGAAUCACUCUGGAGAGCUAUGGAAGGGCCGCUGGCAGGGCAAUGACAUUGUCGUGAAGGUGCUGAAGGUUCGAGACUGGAGUACAAGGAAGAGCAGGGACUUCAAUGAAGAGUGUCCCCGGCUCAGGAUUUUCUCGCAUCCAAAUGUGCUCCCAGUGCUAGGUGCCUGCCAGUCUCCACCUGCUCCUCAUCCUACUCUCAUCACACACUGGAUGCCGUAUGGAUCCCUCUACAAUGUACUACAUGAAGGCACCAAUUUCGUCGUGGACCAGAGCCAGGCUGUGAAGUUUGCUUUGGACAUGGCAAGGGGCAUGGCCUUCCUACACACACUAGAGCCCCUCAUCCCACGACAUGCACUCAAUAGCCGUAGUGUAAUGAUUGAUGAGGACAUGACUGCCCGAAUUAGCAUGGCUGAUGUCAAGUUCUCUUUCCAAUGUCCUGGUCGCAUGUAUGCACCUGCCUGGGUAGCCCCCGAAGCUCUGCAGAAGAAGCCUGAAGACACAAACAGACGCUCAGCAGACAUGUGGAGUUUUGCAGUGCUUCUGUGGGAACUGGUGACACGGGAGGUACCCUUUGCUGACCUCUCCAAUAUGGAGAUUGGAAUGAAGGUGGCAUUGGAAGGCCUUCGGCCUACCAUCCCACCAGGUAUUUCCCCUCAUGUGUGUAAGCUCAUGAAGAUCUGCAUGAAUGAAGACCCUGCAAAGCGACCCAAAUUUGACAUGAUUGUGCCUAUCCUUGAGAAGAUGCAGGACAAGUAGGACUGGAAGGUCCUUGCCUGAACUCCAGAGGUGUCGGGACAUGGUUGGGGGAAUGCACCUCCCCAAAGCAGCAGGCCUCUGGUUGCCUCCCCCGCCUCCAGUCAUGGUACUACCCCAGCCAUGGGGUCCAUCCCCUUCCCCCAUCCCUACCACUGUGGCCCCAAGAGGGGCGGGCUCAGAGCUUUGUCACUUGCCACAUGGUGUCUCCCAACAUGGGAGGGAUCAGCCCCGCCUGUCACAAUAAAGUUUAUUAUGAAAA